AGAAGCGGAGCCGCGAGUCGAGCCGAGCCACUGCCCCCGCUGCCCGCGGGCGCCGGGUGGGGGUCCCGGCGGCUGGAUGGGCAGCGGCGGCGCGGGCCGCGGGCGGCGAUGGGCGAGGAGCAGAGCACGGUGAGCGGCGGCGGCGGGCCCCAGGAGUCGCAGACCCUGGCCAGUGGCACUGCGGGCCACCCUGAGCCCCCGAGGCCUCAGGGGGACAGCGCCCGGGCGCCCCCGCUGCGCGCCGCCUCCGCGGAGCCGAGCGGCGGUGGCUGCGGAAGCGACUGGGGCUGCGCGGACACCAGCGCCCCAGAGCCCGCGAGGAGCCUGGGGCCCCCGGGCUGGAGUAAGAGCCGAGCACCGGCGCAGCCUGCGGGACUGGCACUCACCGGGCCUCUCAAUCCCCAGACCUUGCCACUGCAGUUGGAGCUGGAGGAGGAAGAGGAGGAAGCUGGGGAUCGAAAAGAGGGAGGGGAUGAACAGCAGGAGGCGCCCCCCGGCGAAGAGCUGGAGCCCAGGACCCGCGUGGGGGCCGCCGACGGACUGGUCCUGGACGUGCUGGGUCAGCGGCGCCCGUCCCUCGCCAAGAGACAAGUCUUCUGCUCCGUGUACUGCGUGGAGAGCGACCUGCCCGAGGCCCCCGCCUCGGAGCAGCUCUCGCCGCCCGCGUCGCCACCUGGGGCUCCGCCAGUGUUGAACCCUCCCAGCACCCGCUCUUCCUUCCCCAGCCCCCGACUGUCCCUCCCAACGGAUUCCCUCUCCCCCGACGGCGGCAGCAUCGAGCUGGAGUUCUACCUGGCGCCCGAGCCGUUCUCCAUGCCCAGCCUGUUGGGAGCUCCACCCUACUCUGGCCUGGGCGGUGUAGGGGAUCCCUAUGUGCCCCUCAUGGUGCUGAUGUGCCGGGUGUGCCUGGAAGACAAGCCCAUCAAGCCCCUGCCUUGCUGCAAGAAGGCCGUGUGCGAGGAGUGCCUCAAAGUCUACCUGAGCGCCCAGGUACAACUUGGCCAAGUAGAAAUCAAAUGCCCCAUCACAGAGUGUUUUGAAUUCUUGGAAGAAACAACUGUUGUCUAUAACUUAACGCAUGAAGACUCCAUCAAGUAUAAGUACUUCUUGGAACUUGGCCGUAUUGAUUCCAGCACCAAGCCAUGUCCUCAGUGCAAGCACUUUACAACCUUCAAGAAAAAAGGACAUAUUCCCACCCCUUCCAGAUCAGAAAGCAAAUACAAAAUCCAGUGCCCUACCUGCCAAUUCGUCUGGUGUUUUAAGUGCCACUCUCCUUGGCAUGAAGGUGUUAACUGCAAGGAGUACAAAAAAGGAGACAAAUUGUUGCGUCACUGGGCCAGCGAAAUUGAGCAUGGGCAGAGGAAUGCCCAGAAGUGUCCAAAGUGCAAGAUCCACAUCCAGCGAACUGAAGGAUGUGACCAUAUGACCUGCUCACAAUGUAACACUAAUUUUUGUUACCGAUGUGGUGAGAGAUACCGCCAGCUCCGAUUUUUUGGAGACCACACAUCAAACCUCAGUAUAUUUGGAUGCAAAUAUCGCUACCUCCCAGAGAGACCUCAUUUAAGGAGAUUAGUGCGAGGGUCAGUCUGUGCUGGAAAAUUAUUCAUUGCACCUCUAAUUAUGGUUUUGGGAUUGGCACUAGGGGCCAUAGCGGUUGUAAUCGUUGAGGAAAUUAAGACUUACUGGAACCUCAUAAGUGGUAGAACCAGGAAUCAAACCCAACAUUUGGCUCCACAGCCUGUGUUGUUAAGUGAUAUGCUAUACUGCCUGAAACAAGUGUUUAUUUGUAUUUCCUAUCUAUUGCCUUUGUAAAAAACAGAGAAAACGAUCACGGACAGGUAUGCACUGGUAACAUGCAGAUGAUUUCAUCCAGCUAAGCUGGUUGGAGUAGGAGCGAUACCAAAGGGUACACCCAUCUGUGAGUCACAUCUUGAAAAACACUGAGAGGAACCUUCUACCAUCUCAUCUCCCAGUGAUUCUCCGUGGGCCACAAUGCCUCUAGCUAUGGUGCACUCCCAACAUGGUAUCCUGUCCUUUCCCUAAACAAAUUGCUGCUGCUUUUAAAAAAUGGUCACUUUCAUAAACUAUAAACAUCUAUAUCAUAACUCUGACCUUUGUGGUUCUUGGAAGAAGAUAUUUUAAGAACCAGUUAUCCUAAGAAUUCUGAGCACGCCUCUUCUGAGAAUUGCUUGGACUGUCUUUGAACUCUGCACCUCCUUCCAGGCCAUCUUGUGAGACUUGGUGUUAAUAGCUGAAGUCCUAUCUGUACCAACAAGCAAGGCCACUUUUCAGAAGAUAAGAGUUCACUGAAUGCACCUAUUAUAAUCUGUGGCCCCAGCAGUAUAAUUCUUUUAUCUUUCAAAUGUUAUAAUUGCAAAAAAUCUCAAUGUCCAAAAGGGAAUGAGUGAAACUAAAUUAAUGAGAAGAAUAUUAAGUUACUGAAGUGUAUAUGCGUAGGGGCGUGAAUGUGUGUGUAUAUAAAUAUGUAUUAAAACUAGGCCCAGUAACCUUGUACUUACCCAGUUCCAUGCCGCUACACUAUUUUUCCACAUUUUCAUAGACCUAUUGAAAGAUGAUGGCUCCUUUGUGGACAUAAUUUAGCAAUGUAUUAAAUUAAAGUCAAUGUAGACAACAGGCCAUUUCGAUACUGAACUUUUCUAUUUCUUGCUCUUUCUUUUUGUCACACAAACACAGAAAUUUGUGCAACGUCACCCCAAGGAGUAUUAAGCUUUGUAAACUGACAAAACUGGCUGCUUUUAGGAAAUUCUCAAGACACAAAUAUUCAGUCUUUUUAAAAUUCUUACAUUUUGGAAAACAUGCUUCACUCUAUAGAUAGAUCCUUCACAUUGGGAUUAUUUAAUCCCAAAAACAAGUUUGCUGUAGACAACUGCUUAAGCCUUUAAAAAAUUCCUAUUCUGCUAAUUUUUUAACCAACUUGUAAUUAUAGAUAAUUCUGCUUUAGGUCAAGGUCUUACAUCAUUUAAUAUCCUAACCUUGUUAUCUCUUGCCUCCUCCUCUCUGUUUUUAUUUGUUUUCAAGGUUUUUCAUAAAAACAAAUACUAGUUUUGAAGGAUUUUUUCUUACAUUUAACUGCUCAAACAUAAUAUUUUUGGGGACACCUUCUUAUGGAGGAGUUUGAAAACUUUUUAUGUUCUUGAGUUUGUCCAAUAUCAGCUGCUUUUGGGAAAGGAAACAAAAAAGUGAAGGAAAUAUUUUCAGGAAGUUUUUCUCAACCUACAAAAGCUUUAAAAAUAAGAAAUUGACAAGUAACUAGACUAUGAUAUGCCUUUGCUUUCAUCACAAAAGUUCAUCAGCAAACAGGAAAAAAAAAGACCCCUAAAAAGCCUAAAGCUUUAAAUUGUCUCCAAAUUCUUAAAAUUAGUCAUCUGUCUUAGAUGUACAUUUAUUUGUCAGCAACCUUGUCUGAUUUGAAAUAGAUGAUAUGAUAAAACAUGCAUUAACAUGAGUAGUUUAUUUUUGUUGGGCUCCAGAGUGUAAGAAUAUUUUAUUUUUUGUUUGACAUAAAAAGUGAAGUUGACUUGCGUGAAUAACAAUCCAGCAUGCUUUCAUUCUUUCUGAAUAACACAGAAUAACUGUGCUACAGCUUCUGGAUUAGUUGUCUAUUUCCAGUUAGAGGAGUGUGUGACAUUUAUGGUUUGGGAAUAGCAUAUUUCUAAAGCAUAAUAUAAUACAAGAAAUAGUGAUGCUCUGUUUUCACAAAUUUAUCUUUUCAUUCACCCAUCCAUCCAUUUAACAGAUAUUUAUUGAGUGCCUAUCUUAGGUGUAAUAGUAUUUAAGACUGAAAGAAGGAGAAUUUCUAACCUGUCAUAAGAGUAAGGUUUCGUAAAUUCAUCUUUCCUGAACUUAGGCAUUAGUUUGGCAAUAUGUGAAUAUGAUGAACUCUAAACCUAGCUGAUCUGUAUAUGUAUGAUGUAUAUAUGUCAUAUGUAUGAUAUAUAUGAAAUAUUCCCAUAACUGCAUAUGAACACAUAUGCCAUAUACAUAUAUACCAACGGGCUGAAUAACAUACUCUUUUGUCUUGGAUAAUCUGUUUUCUGGGUUAUGUAUCUGUUGUCUUUGGCCUACUCAGGGAUUUUUAUUUCUUUAAAUAACUUAUCUUUUGGACAUAUUUUUAUAUUAUUUGGAAAACUUUCCAAUAUUCCUGUUACAAAGUGGUGUCUGUUUUCAGUGAUGGCUAUUUCAUCAGUGCUUGAAAUAGUGUGCACUGUGUUGCACAGGUUUUUCAUUUUUCUAUUGAGUAGAUAUUUUUAAAUUAACAUACACAUUUUUCUCUUUAAAGGGUCAUAUCUAUUAGGCCUUUCCCUGCUGGUAACUUAAAAUGAUUAUUUGUGAAUUUUUUACUAAGUUUCAUCAAGAUCUUAAAAAGAGAGAAGAAAAUAAAAAGUAUUAUUUAUAUGUCAGUGCCAACUUUGAAGGUAAAACAGUAGUAGUAACUUUUGGGAGAAAUUCUAAAAACUACUUUAAAAAGAAGCGUGCACAUAAAAUAAAUAUCUUUCUAUCCAAGGCUUGUCAUUUUAUAUGCUUUUAUUGUAAAUUUAAUAUAUACUACUUUAAAAAAUUGAACUAUACAGAAUUUAUAAAAUACAACUUUCUCUACUUACCCCACCUCUUAUUUUCUAGGGGUAACCACUGUUAAUGGUUUGGUAUGUGUCCUUCCAGACACUUUCUACAAAUAUACAAAUAAGUGUGUUUGUGUAUGUGUCUGUGUGUGUAUUCAUUUUAUACAAAUAGAAAAAUAUUCUUACUGUGCUGUGACUCUUUGUCAUUUUAUUAUAUAUUAAUAGAUACCUUUCCAUAAGCGUUUAAAUAGAUUUACCUCAUUCUUUUAUAAAUUACUGCAUAAUCCAUUGUAGGAGUAUACUUUAACUUAUUGAAUUAGUCCCCUGUUGAAUGGACUACAAGAUUAUUUUCACUUCUCUAUUACAAAGAAAGCAAGAGUGAAGACCCUUUUGCAUAUAUUUUUGUCACCUUGCAUGAACAUAUCCAUAAGGUUGUACAUUUGUUUUUUACAAGAUCUUUGUAAUAAACAUUUUAAUGUAAUUUCAGGAGAUGAGGUCAUAGAGAUAAUAUGAGACCCUUUUUUGGAUAAAAAGAAAGAUUGUACAGGAGUGCAUAAUUUUUAAAGAAAAUCGUCUUUUGAAGGGUAAUUUCCUUUCUGCCUGAUUAGCCAAAUAAAUACCUUGCCAAAACUUACAAUAGGAAAUUUUUUUUCAAUAAAAAUAAAAUUUGAGGAGAUGUGUGUCAGAUAAUGUGAGAGAGAUGAAUUGACUUUUGGAUUGCCUCAUUUUAAAACUUGAGGGAUUUAAAUCAAAUACCCAAGCCAAAUUGGUGAUACUUUUCGCAUUUUUAGUAACACUAUCCACUUUUGUGUAUGUUGCUUGACAGAGGAACUUAAUUAUGCCAUUGUGAAAAGUAGGAAAGAAUAUGUUGGCAAUUAUAAAUGCCCACAGCAAUUCCCAGAAAAAUACAUUAGAUUAUGUACGAUUUAGUGAUUUGGUGGGAUAAUUAUAAAUCGUGGAAUAAUUUAUAUAUGUGGAGUAAGAAGAGAGGGGUCAAACCUUUUGGUACAAGCAACAUCUUGUUGCCACCACCUUGAUUUUCUCAUAGGUGCUAUUGUGUCCUAAGAGUAGAACAGACAAGAAAACAAAGAUAAUUAAACACAAGUCAGGUUACAACAUGAUAUCUUUAAUUGUACUUUCUCUGCUGUGGUAUCAAGAUUCAGUGGUGCUUGUCAGAAAAUACCUUGUUCUGUGACUCUGACUAUCUCUUGAGUCCCAAGGCUCCAAUUGAGCCUUUAUCUUUCAACCUUACCACCCAAGUAUAUGACCAACUGUUCUCCUAAAAUACCUAUGAACCACUGUAAUCAUUUCCAGUCCCUGAUGCCCCUCUUCAACCUCAUUUUUCUCCAUACCUCUGCUAUUCUAACUAUUCCUCUUCACUGAAGGAGAAGAGGAGAGACAGGAGGGGCCUAAAAACUCACUCUGGUAUGUGGGAAACAUUAGAAUUCCUUCCUGACCUUUGUCAAAUGAGGGCACAUCUGCCAAGACAUCAGUCCAGCUUCUCCCUUGUUAAAUGAAAUUGUUUUUAACAUUACACUUUUAUACUGGCUGUUACAUUAGAAUUACAAAAAAGUUAGUGGCCUCUAUAACCUUAAUUGGCAUACUUUACUACAAAAAUAAGAAAAUGUAUGCCAAAAAACGUUUUUAGAUUUUAAUUUUAUAAGCAACCUGCACAUAAGCCUUAAUGUGAGUCUUCACAUUGGAUUAUAUUUUUAUUCUCCCAUAUUUGUGGCUGAAAUCUCUCCCAACUAUUGAGAGUGAUCUUUCCCAUGGUCUGCUUUAUUGUUUUGUGUUAAUAUCUAUUAUAAAUAUAGCCUUAAAAUUUUGUAAUGCACUUUAAAAUAUUUGUGCCAUUUAAAUAAUGACAAAGCAAUCAAUGCAUACAUUUCAAUGGAGACAGUAUACAAAGUUAAAGCAACUGAUACAUAUAUUUCAGUGGAGACAGUAGGAUAACAGUGUUAGCAAAUAUGUGUCAUCUCUUUAAAUUUGGGAGGAAUCAGAAGCUAAAGAUUUAAAACAAAUAAAACAUACCUGAAGAAAAGUAGCAAUUUCUGAAAUUGUAGUAAUCUUGGAAUGGUUAUCAAACCUAGCAAAUAAUACUUAAUAAGUGUUACCUAAUAUACCUAAUUGGAAUGUUUGUUUAAAAUAUUAAAUUAAUUUAUACUGAAAGUUUUAACUGCAAUUUCAUAAUUCAUGAAUUCUAUAAAAGAAAUCUCCCUCACUAAAAAUAUGAUCAAUCAAAACUACCAGUUUUGCACACCAAUCCCAAGUUUAAGCAUAUUUUGUAUUUAAAGUUAUAAUUUAAUUAUGAUACUGUCCCCCUAAUAUGGAAAAUAAGUUACAAAAUUCUUUUUUUUUUUUUUUUUUUUUUGAGACAGAGGUUCUCUCAAUGUUGCCCAGGCUGGUCUCAAACUCUUGGGCUCAAGCGAUCCUCCCUCCUCUGCCUCUGGAGUAGCUGGGAUUACAAGCACGUGCCUACUAUGCCUGUCUUCAAAAUCACAUUGUUAAUUUUUAUAGCCACAAUUAUUAAUUUGAUAAAACAAAUAAUUUUAUAGAAGCAUUAAAGUAUUAUCAGAACAAAAUCAGAGUUCCAAAAUUUGGGGAGUAUUUUAAGAUUGUGAAAUGUUACCUUUUGGAUGCAAACCAAUGAUACAAAUCUUUAAGAAAGAAUUACAGUGGGACUCCUUUGAAACUCUGAUUUUGAAAAUAGAACAAAUACACAUUUCAUAGCCAAACUUUGUGUGGGACUUCUAUUGUUACUAAUUGUAAGGCUGUAACUUUGGUUGACUUCAUCCAAAUCCAAGAAACAGAGUCACAGUAGUGAGACUAUUCUCAUUGCUUCUUUGGAGCAUUAGCUGAAGCUUUACCAUAUCACAUACCUUACAAAAUCCCUAUACAUAUUGCCAGUUUUAAAAGAAUGUAAUUAUGCAUGUUACAAACUAUAUAUAUCUUUUUGGCUAGAGAAGUGACUAUUUUAGAAUAACAGUAUGAAUGUAAAAGGCAAUAAUUUUUUUUAAAUACACAAAACAUUGCCAUUGCCCUUUUUUGUCACUUCCUUUUUUCUUCUAAAAAUUUUCAUUUGGUGUAUCUAACUUUGUAUCACUUAAAUUAUUCAGACUUACUAAGAUAAAAAAUACUUUUUUUCAGUUCUGUGCUAUAUUCUGUCACUCUAUUCCAUUAUUAAUACUAAAUGACUUUCCUUGUGAAAUGAUACCCACAUACUACAACAUCAAGCUCCUUUUUCUCUUAAAUUUCCUAAUUAUCUUGAUUUUUGCCUCUGCAGUCUUCUUCCCAUCUUGGCCAAGUGUGGGAUAAAUUCUGUCUCGCCCGUAACUCCUUUCACUGUAAUGAAAUGAAUUCAACACUGAACGCACUCCAGAAUUUAGCUCUGGUAGUGAGCAUAAUUUACCUUGGCUUAUUUUAUUUGUAAAUGGAAAUGUAUCAGGAGUGCCUGGAACACUUUUCCCUCUUGAUAGGAGUUGGAGAACACUGCCUAGCCCUCUGCCAAGAAGUAAGUCAAGCAAAUGAAGAUACCAGUUGGAUCAGAGGGCCUAAUAAUAGUCUAAAACCAAGCUUCAGAAAUUGCUUCGUGACUGUUGUAAGAUCAAUAUUGUGUUUGCGUAUUAGUUGGACAGAAAGCAUGUGUGGACAUUCAUCCAACCUGACCCCAGGUCAUUCAUUCUCCAUCCAAAAAGGGUUAUAGGUAUGGUUUAUGGUCUUUGUUUCAGCAAAACGUCCUACAGCUUGGACUUGGGGUGGAUUUAUAUAGUGUAGCAUUUGUAUAUAAGAUUCAAUUAUGGAUUCAUGCUCUGUGAACAUUGUUAGAUUUUUAAUAAUCUAAAGUAGGUCACAUUGAAUGUAACUGAUAUUAACCCUAUUCUAGAGAAAACAUUUGUCAUUUGCAAGUGUUUGACUUUUUUAUUGAUAUGAUUUAGAUAUGCCACACUCAAUAUAUUUAGUAUAGAUUCAGUACAUAACAGGAAAGAAAAAGGGAGAGACAGACUUGAGUGUUAAAGGACCCCAGAAAUUGCUGAAAUGUCCUUUUAGAUUCUUGUGGCUGGCAAGCUAUGCUGUCAUUGGUUCUCUGCGAAUCUGUGAUGUGUUCACUUCGCCAUGCCCCAGCUUGGGAAAUAUUCUUAGUAAUCCAAUCAAAUCCUUAAAAACAGCAUUUUUGUGAAUGUAUUACUUCUUCAAUAUCCCCAUAUAUUUGUAUUGUUUCAAGCCACUAGUAUCUAAAUUUUUGAUAUAAAUAUCUAAAUUCUUUCAUUUUAUAGAAAAUUAGCAUGCUUUAUGUUUCUUUAUAAUGAAAAGUCUAGAUAAAGUAUCAUAAUUUCAUUAUCAGCUGACAAGAAACCCUUCUAAGACCCAUUUUUUUAAGUGUCAUAUGGCAACUCCUCAAUAGCUUACUUUUAUUAUUUGAUCAUUUUCAUCACAAUUGCAAUCCUCUAGAGGGUAUUUUAAAAAGUAGACCAACCUUAUGUUUCACGUGAAACAUAGAAUAAUAAUUAGUUUGUAUAUAUAUAAAACCAUUUACCUUGACAAGGACAAUCUGUUACAGAUUUUUAAUAUGAAAAUUGACAAUUUUGUUGCUUUUAGAAGCAAUUAACAUAGUAAUUAGUAAAUUCUGAGAGAUGACAGAAAUGAUUUUCUGUAGAAGGAACACAACAGUGAUGUUAAAAUGUUAACAAAGAACCAGUUGUUUUGAUUCUAUUUUAAACAAAAUUGUAAGGCAAUUUUAUGAAACAAACAUUUAUAUCAAUGUAUAUCUAUUUCAAAACUGUGGGACAAUUAUUCAUUCUUUUCCCAAAUAGAGUAAAAUAUUAAAGAGAAAAAAAUUCGAGUGUUUAUCUGUUAUUACUGUAUAUUCAGAAAUUACAGUUCUAAGGAAUUAUUGUCAUCCUCUAAGUAUCAGAAUGUAUUCCAUUUUAAUUAUAUUCUCCUUAACAAUAGAAAAUUAGAAGAAAUUUCUUGAUCAUAAGAUGAAUAGUAAUUUGUACCAGAUCUUGUCCAUCAUUUCAUUAGAUUGCAUAUUUUUAGUUUUCUAUAAAAUUUGCAGCCAUUUUCCAAAUAAAGUAAGUUAUAAUAUUUUUCAAGUUUAAAAUGGACCGGGUUGAAAAGAGAUUUCAUUGAUUCUUUUUAAUGAUAUUGGAAAAUAUUUAUGCAAUUUUAUUUUUUAACCUUUUCUCCAUUUCAUUAGUUAUACUAUUAACUUUGAUAAUCACAAAACUAUGUGGAAGAAAUCAUUCUGAUUAUAUUUUAUGAAAGAGAGGGGUAGAGUAAAUUUUUUAAUUAGACAAUGUUGAUAUGCAGAAAUCUCUCAAAAGAAAUUGCAAAGGAAAAAUUACGUUGAGAUGAAAUGUUGAGAAAUAAGGAGUAUCUUAAAAACCUAAUUUCUUACACUUUUUAGAGCAAUCAACUUAUUUCCAAAUUAUUAUUUCAUGCUGUUGUUUCCAUGAAUUGUGUUUUUAGCAUAGUAUAUACUUUUCUACCACGUUAGCAUUUACACUCUAAUUACUGAAAAUAAAGGAAGAAGUUGGUGAAUAAAAGCCAGGGAAACUGGGUUUAUUCUCAUUUUCCAAUAGCACUAAUGUAUAAUCCCUUUAACCUUCCAUAUGGUGCUUUGUGUGAUGAGUAUAUAACAUUCAUAUACGUUAUUAGUGCCUUAUUUUUUUCACUUGACUUUAUUUCUUAUCUAAAGAGCCAUAUAUUUUUUGUGAGUGUUCUUUGGUCCCUCUAUUUAAAGUGCUAAGGAGAAAGCAUAUCUUUAGGGAUGUAUAUAGGCUGCGUUUGCUACCUUAAUCUACUGUAUUAUCUCUAAAACAGGUUAGCCAAUGUAUUUUUCUUAAAUUCAUUGUUCAUUUUUAAGCUAACCUAUACAAAUGGAUAUUAAACACCAGAAAUUAAAGCCAUUAAAAUUGAAUUGUACUUUAAAACCAUAAAAAAUGCUAAUUAAGUUUAGAACAGGAGUUGAAAUGACUCUCAGUUUUAUCUAUAGCUCCAAUUAGGACAAAAUUACUUUACAAAAAGCAUUAAAAAUAAAAGUAACUGUAUGGUACUUCAGGAAUUUGACCAGUUCCUUACAACUUAUUCUUGGCAAUAUUUUGUCAGUAAUAUACUUUCAUACAGAUGCUAGAGAACCAUGGUGUCUGCUAUUUACAUGUUAUUUGUUCCCAGUGAGCUUUAUCAACAUCAACCCUGUUUAUAUAAUAUGUUAUUUUGCUCUUCUUGAUCUGUGCCUUUUGUUUUAGCUUUAUACAAAAUGCUAGGUUUGUUAUAUUCUUUAUGUAUCAUAAUAUAUAAUUCAACUUUUCCUGAUGAAUGUAUGCUGAAUAAUUAAACUAAACCAUGUGCUUAGAAAAGACAAAGACAGGUUGUAUAUGCAGUUAUGUGUAAAUAUUUGACAAAGAAAAAAAAAGGAAAAGAAUCUUCCUGCCAACAGGUAGGUCCUGCUGGACAGGACCUGAAAAUUAAGAGAUUUUUUUUUUUAAGCAGUGAAAUUUAAAAAUCUAUUACCUCAAGAAUUUUCAGUCGAUAUGUCAAUGUACUGUUCCUUCUCAGUAAGUACAGUGUCACAUGCUGCUGGCGGUAAAAGCAACCCAAGUGUCAGAUCACACAAAUUUUAGGGACAAGUCUUUCAAAAGACGGACACCUUGUGAUAUUUUGGAGUCUAAUUUCCGACUUUUCGUAAUGUCCCAAUGACCUUUUGUUGUGGUUGGGCUUUUAUAAAAAAUUAUUUUCGGUUGGUUGUUGUAGAAUGGAAGAGUAAUCUUAAUUAUGAAAUCAGAUUGCAUGGAAGAAUAUAAAGACACUCACUCGGAUGAAAACUAUAACGGUUUUCAAACUAUUUUGAUGGUCAUUGUACGAGCUAUUGUAUGGAUUACUGUGGAGUGCUGUUUACCACAUGAUGUGUGCAAUACAUCAUGCAAUGUUAUUUAGCAAUGCGUAAUAAAAGUUUUUAAAAGAGAAAA